ACUGUGCUGGAACUCUCUGCCGAGGAGGGUGGAGUGUCUGGGCUCCGCUGCUCCCACAAAGCAAGCAUUUUCCUGUUUUCUUGGAGGCAGUUUAUUACAGAUUUCAACCCUUUCUGCAUCCCUCCCUCCCUUACAACACGCACACUCAUCUUUUCUUGCAUUACUGCUGAAAUUAUGCAAACUUCGUUUCUCUGUCAUCUGAGCGUCAUUCAGAAAUGUUCCUCCGAUCUGUGAAUUGUUCCCUGACUUCAAUCGGGGCAGUGUUACAGGUCCUCUGCUGGCAGGAGGGAGCAGUCCGUGAAAAUCUGCAGACACAAGACUUUCAGAAGCUGUGACGAGCAGACUAGCAAGCCACAAAACAUUGCAAGCUGAAUGGAUGUCUUAAUAAGCUUUUAGAUGUGAUUUGGCCAGCAUCAGCAGAGGAGGCUAACGGGAAAAGGCAGCGAACAUUGUAACGUAAAUCACUGCAGAUUUGCUGGGAGUGACAGCCCUAGGAAGCUAAUGAUCUCUCCAGGAAAGAAUUGACCACAGUUAUCCAGAAACUGAACACGAUGUAGAACAGAGAGGACAGCCCCUCGGAUGUCCCGAAGAUGGCAUAUUCAUAAAGACAUCUUCUGAUGAUUGUGAACAUCUUUACCUCUGGGUGCCAGGCCGGGCCAGUGACUUCGUGUUGAGCUGAAGGAACUUGUCUACCGCUUCCCUGAAAACCUUUCUUUCCUAAUUCAUGAGCCAGCAAGAUGCGGUCGCUGCACUUUCAGAGCGCCUUCUCGUAGCUGCGUACAAAGGCCAAACAGAGAAUGUGGUUCAGCUCAUCAACAAGGGCGCCAGGGUAGCGGUUACCAAGCAUGGCCGGACUCCCCUGCAUCUUGCUGCCAAUAAGGGCCAUCUUCCUGUGGUCCAGAUCUUGCUGAAGGCUGGCUGCGACCUUGAUGUCCAGGAUGAUGGGGACCAGACCGCCUUGCACCGGGCCACAGUGGUGGGGAACACGGAGAUCAUCGCGGCGCUCAUCCACGAAGGGUGUGCCCUGGACAGACAAGACAAGGAUGGGAAUACAGCCUUGCAUGAAGCAUCCUGGCAUGGUUUCAGCCAGUCAGCCAAGCUGCUCAUUAAAGCAGGAGCCAACGUGCUUGCCAAGAACAAGGCGGGGAACACAGCUCUGCACCUGGCCUGCCAGAACAGCCACUCCCAGAGCACGCGCGUCCUCCUGCUGGCCGGGUCCCGCGCUGACCUCAAAAAUAAUGCAGGAGACACCUGUUUGCACGUUGCUGCGCGCUAUAAUCACUUGUCCAUCAUUAGGCUCCUCCUCACUGCUUUCUGUUCUGUCCAUGAAAAGAACCAGGCUGGAGACACAGCACUUCACGUUGCUGCUGCCCUAAAUCACAAGAAGGUGGCCAAAAUCUUACUGGAAGCCGGAGCAGAUACGACCAUUGUUAACAAUGCAGGCCAGACUCCGCUGGAGACUGCCCGCUACCACAAUAACCCGGAAGUUGCUCUUCUCCUUACUAAAGCUCCCCAGGUCUUGCGCUUCAGUCGUGGGCGAAGCCUGAGGAAAAAGAGAGAGAGGCUCAAGGAAGAGAGGAGAGCCCAGUCUGUGCCAAGAGAUGAGGUGGCCCAAAGCAAGGGCAGUGUCUCAGCAGGAGACACCCCCAGCAGUGAACAGGCUGUGGCCAGAAAAGAAGAAGCCAGAGAAGAGUUCCUGUCAGCCUCCCCAGAACCCAGAGCAAAGGAUGACAGGAGGAGAAAGUCAAGGCCCAAGGUGUCAGCAUUUUCUGACCCCACCCCACCAGCCGACCAACAGCCUGGACACCAGAAGAACCUGCAUGCUCAUAAUCACCCUAAAAAGAGGAACAGGCAUCGGUGUUCAUCCCCACCCCCACCCCAUGAGUUCAGGGCGUAUCAGCUCUACACAUUGUACCGGGGCAAGGAUGGGAAAGUGAUGCAGGCACCAAUAAAUGGUUGUCGAUGUGAACCUCUAAUCAACAAGCUGGAGAAUCAGUUGGAGGCUACUGUGGAGGAGAUAAAAGCAGAGCUGGGAUCGGUUCAGGACAAAAUGAAUACAAAGCUGGGGCAGAUGGAGAAUAAGACCCAGCACCAAAUGCGUGUUUUGGACAAGCUGAUGGUUGAGCGACUUUCUGCAGAGAGGACGGAGUGCCUGAACCGCCUGCAACAGCACUCAGACACAGAGAAGCAUGAGGGGGAGAAACGACAGAUAUCCUUGGUGGAUGAAUUAAAAACCUGGUGCAUGUUAAAGAUUCAGAAUCUGGAGCAGAAGCUUUCUGGAGAUUCUAGGGCCUGCAGAGCUAAAUCCACACCAUCUACUUGUGAGUCCUCUACAGGUGUGGACCAAUUAGUGGUGACUGCAGGUCCAGCAGCAGCUUCCGACAGCUCCCCUCCAGUGGUUAGGCCCAAAGAGAAGGCCCUCAACUCCACUGCUACCCAGAGACUCCAGCAGGAGCUGUCGUCUUCUGACUGUACAGGCUCCCGACUGAGAAACGUCAAGGUCCAGACAGCCUUGCUACCCAUGAAUGAGGCAGCCAGAUCUGAUCAGCAGGCUGGGCCCUGCGUCAACAGAGGCACUCAAACUAAGAAGUCUGGGAAGAGUGGGCCAACAAGGCAUCGUGCCCAGCAACCCGCAGCCAGCAGCACCUGUGGGCAGCCGCCACCAGCCACAGGCAGCGAGCAGACUGGCCCUCACAUUCGGGACACCUCCCAAGCUCUGGAGCUUACCCAGUAUUUUUUUGAGGCUGUUUCUACCCAGAUGGAAAAGUGGUAUGAAAGGAAGAUUGAAGAAGCACGAAGCCAAGCCAAUCAGAAAGCCCAGCAAGAUAAGGCUACAUUGAAGGAACACAUUAAAAGUUUAGAAGAGGAACUUGCCAAACUAAGGACUAGGGUGCAGAAGGAAAAUUAGCACCAAUAAAGAGGAAAUAUGAAAGGAUUCUUGAAGAUUUCCAGUUUUGCAACUGCAUAAUAGCUAUGCCCAAGGAGUCAACUAUUGUAUAUAUUGCAGAUUUGCCUUUUUAAAAAAAUCACUAAUUCUACAAUGUGCCAGAUACAUGUUUCCUAUGCCCAGGAAGUUAUGAAGACUUCAACAAUUAAACUGAAACCAGGGGAAGCUUGCUUAGUUUUGGGUUUCAUUAUAAACUCUUAGCCUCAGUCCAGGUUAAUCUGAAGUUUGAAAGCUCAGAUUAAGCAAGCCAUGCCAAGAAACUGGACGAUGUGUAAGCCUAGACUCUAAAAUUCAAGAUGUGUGAAAUAAUAUAAGUCAAAAGCAAGAAAAACGUAAUCCCGUCUGAACUCAAGUAGUCAUUCAUAUAAAUUUGAACACACCUGCUGUGCCUAGACAAGUGUCUUUCUGUAAGAGCUGUAACUCUGAGAUGUGCUAAAUAAACCCUCUUUCUCAAAUUCGUAAUUCUCCAACUGUUGACAUUUUAAUCACAUGAAAAGUUAUCAGAUUUUUGAGGAGAAAUAUUUUCAUGAUGUCACAAGAUCCAAUAUAUCUUAUGAUAAAAUUUAUUGAAAAGUCAGUUUAUUUAAAUAAUGAAUAAUUGGCUAACAGCUCUGGAAACAAUGAGAUCAAAUGAGAAAGAUUCAAAUUGUUUGUUAUUUUCUGUAUUUUCAGUCAAAAAAUCAGUUAUAUAGUGAUUUUAAAGCAGAUUAAUGGAAAAAAAUUCAUGUAACAAUUACCUGAAAAUUUAUAACCUAUUCCUAAUCAAACCCAAUUAUAUCAGAAUACCUUUCUGAAUUUGAGAUUUUUGCUCUACAUUUUAUAAUGAAUAAGGCUAUUUUUUGAAAGUAUUUCAUUUUGAAUUCUGUCAUUAACCUCAAAAGCUUUCUACUGCUUUGCGGUGAAGGCAAAAUAUUCGAUAACUCAACUUAGGCCCCACUGUUCCCCAACUUCAUGGAGGCCAGAAGACUUUACUUUGUUCCAUAAUGAAAUAUAAACACAGAACAAAGUUGUAAAAGUAGCAUGGAUAUGUUGAAACUUUGGACAAGCUUCUUGUCCUUUGGAAUAUGGGAUUUAUAUUCAUCUCCUCAAUAUCCCAUGUAUGCACAGAAACUUCAGUUCUAUUUCUAUAGACACAGGAACCUAGUGACUAUUGAACGUAAUUGUAAUAAAAUGCUGCUCAUUGAGCCAAAGAGAAGAAAUGAUUUAUUAACAUGGGGACACCAAGAAAAACAAAGUAUGCUUUUAUUCCCUUUGUCAAGCUCAGUUUUAGGGUUUUUUCUUUUUUUUAUAGUGACAAUCCAUAGAUAUAGACAUUCCUAAAAGAAAAAUAAUUCAGUAGAUAUAUGUCACUGUUACCUGAAUAUGGAAUGAAUUUGAUGUUUUUUAUUUUGUUGAGACAGGGUCUUGCUCUGUCACCCAGACUGGAGUGCAGUGGCAUGAUCACACCUCACUGCAGCCUUGGCCUCUCAGGCUCGUGAUCCUCCUGCCUCAACCUCGCAAGUAGCUUGGGACUACAGGCGUGUGCCACCAGUCCUGGCUAAUUUUUUGUAGAUAUAAGGUCUCAUGAUAUUGCCCAGGCUGAAUUUGAUGUUAUUUCAAGUUGAUUUUCAUGUGUUUGGGAGCUUGUCUUGUUCUCAACUACUACGCAGGUAGACAGUCUUCCCCCAGAGACUCAUUAGAUUGCAAUAUAGAGGCACUUUCUCAUUUCCCUAUUGUUCCUAAUACAGAAUUGUAGAGCUGGAGAGUACCUUCAGUUUUCUAAAUCUAUUCUCAAACAGGAUAUCACUAACCUCUUUAGAAUCAUUCCUCAGUAUACAUCAAUUUAUUGAGAACUGCCUAAUACUCAAGAAAUUAAAUCCUGAGUUCAGUAGGCUGUGUUCCAAGCAGGAAUUAUUUUCACUUACCAAAAUAUCUCCUAUUACCUCAAGGUAUCCUUGUUGAGGAAUGCUGAAAACUAAAUUUUAAGUAUCAAGUCUAGACCAUAGAGUGCUUUGGUGGGAGUAUUUUGAUUACCUCCUACCCAUCAGAAGCAGGCAGCUAAUAUUGUGAACUGAGUAUUUUUGUCAAAAGUCACAGGGAAGAGACUACAGAAGAAUGAGAAGGGUCAAAAGGACCUAGUGUGGCUUACUACAUGGAUCUUGUCUCUUGGAGGUCUGUCGUAGAAGAAGAAACAAAUAGAGGUGAUGAAGACACAGAACAGGCUCAGUCAGCAUCCUCACCCAGAGAUGGCAACAUCUAUUAAGACCAAUGCAAUACCUUUUCAUCUUCAGCAAAUGUUGUUUCAUCUGUUUUUGAUCCUUGGCAUUGUCAAAAACUUAACUGCAGGUCCAGUGUAUAUUUUUCCUUAUUUUUCCCUUUUAGCUAUCUGCUAAAGUGAGUAAAUGCCACAACUGUACUUUUCCAAAGAAAAAGAACUAUUGACAACUUAUAGCCUGUCAUGCAGGUCAUGUUUCAAAUCAAGGCUGAAAUUUUCAACAGCUGUGGGAAAAACUAAAACACAGAAAUACUGUACAGUAUUAGUGUUUUUUUAAAGAAAUUGUUAGUGCAUUAUUGAGUAUACUAAAUAUCUGUGAUUAAAUAAAUUAGUUCUAACUUUUGAUUUUGGGAGCCCAAAAUAAAGGGAGUGUUGUUUUCAUGGUUAUGCCUUGUUUGUGGAGUCAAGUGUUGAUAUACUUGAGGCAUGUUAUGUGUCUUCUAAUUAAUAUUUUUAUCACCUUGAAUUUGUGUCUCUUCCAAGCAUUAAAGAUACUAUGGAUCUUAAAUUCCUUAUUAAAAAAAUGCAAGUGUGAAU